GCCGCUGUCGCUGUCGCCGAGCCCAGUCGAGCCGCGCUCACCUCGGGCUCCCGCUCCGUCUCCACCUCCGCCUUUGCCCUGGCGGCGCGACCCCGUCCCGGGCGCGGCCCCCAGCAGUCGCGCGCCGUUAGCCUCGCGCCCGCCGCGCAGUCCGGGCCCGGCGCGAUGGGGGCCGCCGCCGGCCGGAGCCCCCACCUGGGGCCCGCGCCCGCCCGCCGCCCGCAGCGCUCUCUGCUCCUGCUGCAGCUGCUGCUGCUCGUCGCUGCCCCGGGGUCCACGCAGGCCCAGGCCGCCCCGUUCCCCGAGCUGUGCAGUUAUACAUGGGAAGCUGUUGAUACCAAAAAUAAUGUACUUUAUAAAAUCAACAUCUGUGGAAGUGUGGAUAUUGUCCAGUGCGGGCCAUCAAGUGCUGUUUGUAUGCACGACUUGAAGACACGCACUUAUCAUUCAGUGGGUGACUCUGUUUUGAGAAGUGCAACCAGAUCUCUCCUGGAAUUCAACACAACAGUGAGCUGUGACCAGCAAGGCACAAAUCACAGAGUCCAGAGCAGCAUUGCCUUCCUGUGUGGGAAAACCCUGGGAACUCCUGAAUUUGUAACUGCAACAGAAUGUGUGCACUACUUUGAGUGGAGGACCACUGCAGCCUGCAAGAAAGACAUAUUUAAAGCAAAUAAGGAGGUGCCAUGCUAUGUGUUUGAUGAAGAGUUGAGGAAGCAUGAUCUCAAUCCUCUGAUCAAGCUUAGUGGUGCCUACUUGGUGGAUGACUCCGAUCCGGACACUUCUCUAUUCAUCAAUGUUUGUAGAGACAUAGACACACUACGAGACCCAGGUUCACAGCUGCGGGCCUGUCCCCCCGGCACUGCCGCCUGCCUGGUAAGAGGACACCAGGCGUUUGAUGUUGGCCAGCCCCGGGACGGACUGAAGCUGGUGCGCAAGGACAGGCUUGUCCUGAGUUACGUGAGGGAAGAGGCAGGAAAGCUAGACUUUUGUGAUGGUCACAGCCCUGCGGUGACUAUUACAUUUGUUUGCCCGUCGGAGCGGAGAGAGGGCACCAUUCCCAAACUCACAGCUAAAUCCAACUGCCGCUAUGAAAUUGAGUGGAUUACUGAGUAUGCCUGCCACAGAGAUUACCUGGAAAGUAAAACUUGUUCUCUGAGCGGCGAGCAGCAGGAUGUCUCCAUAGACCUCACACCACUUGCCCAGAGCGGAGGUUCAUCCUAUAUUUCAGAUGGAAAAGAAUAUUUGUUUUAUUUGAAUGUCUGUGGAGAAACUGAAAUACAGUUCUGUAAUAAAAAACAAGCUGCAGUUUGCCAAGUGAAAAAGAGCGAUACCUCUCAAGUCAAAGCAGCAGGAAGAUACCACAAUCAGACCCUCCGAUAUUCGGAUGGAGACCUCACCUUGAUAUAUUUUGGAGGUGAUGAAUGCAGCUCAGGGUUUCAGCGGAUGAGCGUCAUAAACUUUGAGUGCAAUAAAACCGCAGGUAACGAUGGGAAAGGAACUCCUGUAUUCACAGGGGAGGUUGACUGCACCUACUUCUUCACAUGGGACACGGAAUACGCCUGUGUUAAGGAGAAGGAAGACCUCCUCUGCGGUGCCACCGACGGGAAGAAGCGCUAUGACCUGUCCGCGCUGGUCCGCCAUGCAGAACCAGAGCAGAAUUGGGAAGCUGUGGAUGGCAGUCAGACGGAAACAGAGAAGAAGCAUUUUUUCAUUAAUAUUUGUCACAGAGUGCUGCAGGAAGGCAAGGCACGAGGGUGUCCCGAGGACGCGGCAGUGUGUGCAGUGGAUAAAAAUGGAAGUAAAAAUCUGGGAAAAUUUAUUUCCUCUCCCAUGAAAGAGAAAGGAAACAUUCAACUCUCUUAUUCAGAUGGUGAUGAUUGUGGUCAUGGCAAGAAAAUUAAAACUAAUAUCACACUUGUAUGCAAGCCAGGUGAUCUGGAAAGUGCACCAGUGUUGAGAACUUCUGGGGAAGGCGGUUGCUUUUAUGAGUUUGAGUGGCACACAGCUGCGGCCUGUGUGCUGUCUAAGACAGAAGGGGAGAACUGCACGGUCUUUGACUCCCAGGCAGGGUUUUCUUUUGACUUAUCACCUCUCACAAAGAAAAAUGGUGCCUAUAAAGUUGAGACAAAGAAGUAUGACUUUUAUAUAAAUGUGUGUGGCCCGGUGUCUGUGAGCCCCUGUCAGCCAGACUCAGGAGCCUGCCAGGUGGCAAAAAGUGAUGAGAAGACUUGGAACUUGGGUCUGAGUAAUGCGAAGCUUUCAUAUUAUGAUGGGAUGAUCCAACUGAACUACAGAGGCGGCACACCCUAUAACAAUGAAAGACACACACCGAGAGCUACGCUCAUCACCUUUCUCUGUGAUCGAGACGCGGGAGUGGGCUUCCCUGAAUAUCAGGAAGAGGAUAACUCCACCUACAACUUCCGGUGGUACACCAGCUAUGCCUGCCCGGAGGAGCCCCUGGAAUGCGUAGUGACCGACCCCUCCACGCUGGAGCAGUACGACCUCUCCAGUCUGGCAAAAUCUGAAGGUGGCCUUGGAGGAAACUGGUAUGCCAUGGACAACUCAGGGGAACAUGUCACGUGGAGGAAAUACUACAUUAACGUGUGUCGGCCUCUGAAUCCAGUGCCGGGCUGCAACCGAUAUGCAUCGGCUUGCCAGAUGAAGUAUGAAAAAGAUCAGGGCUCCUUCACUGAAGUGGUUUCCAUCAGUAACUUGGGAAUGGCAAAGACCGGCCCGGUGGUUGAGGACAGCGGCAGCCUCCUUCUGGAAUACGUGAAUGGGUCGGCCUGCACCACCAGCGAUGGCAGACAGACCACAUAUACCACGAGGAUCCAUCUCGUCUGCUCCAGGGGCAGGCUGAACAGCCACCCCAUCUUUUCUCUCAACUGGGAGUGUGUGGUCAGUUUCCUGUGGAACACAGAGGCUGCCUGUCCCAUUCAGACAACGACGGAUACAGACCAGGCUUGCUCUAUAAGGGAUCCCAACAGUGGAUUUGUGUUUAAUCUUAAUCCGCUAAACAGUUCGCAAGGAUAUAACGUCUCUGGCAUUGGGAAGAUUUUUAUGUUUAAUGUCUGCGGCACAAUGCCUGUCUGUGGGACCAUCCUGGGAAAACCUGCUUCUGGCUGUGAGGCAGAAACCCAAACUGAAGAGCUCAAGAAUUGGAAGCCAGCAAGGCCAGUCGGAAUUGAGAAAAGCCUCCAGCUGUCCACAGAGGGCUUCAUCACUCUGACCUACAAAGGGCCUCUCUCUGCCAAAGGUACCGCUGAUGCUUUUAUCGUCCGCUUUGUUUGCAAUGAUGAUGUUUACUCAGGGCCCCUCAAAUUCCUGCAUCAAGAUAUCGACUCUGGGCAAGGGAUCCGAAACACUUACUUUGAGUUUGAAACCGCGUUGGCCUGUGUUCCUUCUCCAGUGGACUGCCAAGUCACCGACCUGGCUGGAAAUGAGUACGACCUGACUGGCCUAAGCACAGUCAGGAAACCUUGGACGGCUGUUGACACCUCUGUCGAUGGGAGAAAGAGGACUUUCUAUUUGAGCGUUUGCAAUCCUCUCCCUUACAUUCCUGGAUGCCAGGGCAGCGCAGUGGGGUCUUGCUUAGUGUCAGAAGGCAAUAGCUGGAAUCUGGGUGUGGUGCAGAUGAGUCCCCAAGCCGCGGCGAAUGGAUCUUUGAGCAUCAUGUAUGUCAACGGUGACAAGUGUGGGAACCAGCGCUUCUCCACCAGGAUCACGUUUGAGUGUGCUCAGAUAUCGGGCUCACCAGCAUUUCAGCUUCAGGAUGGUUGUGAGUACGUGUUUAUCUGGAGAACUGUGGAAGCCUGUCCCGUUGUCAGAGUGGAAGGGGACAACUGUGAGGUGAAAGACCCAAGGCAUGGCAACUUGUAUGACCUGAAGCCCCUGGGCCUCAACGACACCAUCGUGAGCGCUGGCGAAUACACUUAUUACUUCCGGGUCUGUGGGAAGCUUUCCUCAGACGUCUGCCCCACAAGUGACAAGUCCAAGGUGGUCUCCUCAUGUCAGGAAAAGCGGGAACCGCAGGGAUUUCACAAAGUGGCAGGUCUCCUGACUCAGAAGCUAACUUAUGAAAAUGGCUUGUUAAAAAUGAACUUCACGGGGGGGGACACUUGCCAUAAGGUUUAUCAGCGCUCCACAGCCAUCUUCUUCUACUGUGACCGCGGCACCCAGCGGCCAGUAUUUCUAAAGGAGACUUCAGAUUGUUCCUACUUGUUUGAGUGGCGAACGCAGUAUGCCUGCCCACCUUUCGAUCUGACUGAAUGUUCAUUCAAAGAUGGGGCUGGCAACUCCUUCGACCUCUCGUCCCUGUCAAGGUACAGUGACAACUGGGAAGCCAUCACUGGGACGGGGGACCCGGAGCACUACCUCAUCAAUGUCUGCAAGUCUCUGGCCCCGCAGGCUGGCACUGAGCCGUGCCCUCCAGAAGCAGCCGCGUGUCUGCUGGGUGGCUCCAAGCCCGUGAACCUCGGCAGGGUAAGGGACGGACCUCAGUGGAGAGAUGGCAUAAUUGUCCUGAAAUACGUUGAUGGCGACUUAUGUCCAGAUGGGAUUCGGAAAAAGUCAACCACCAUCCGAUUCACCUGCAGCGAGAGCCAAGUGAACUCCAGGCCCAUGUUCAUCAGCGCCGUGGAGGACUGUGAGUACACCUUUGCCUGGCCCACAGCCACAGCCUGUCCCAUGAAGAGCAACGAGCAUGAUGACUGCCAGGUCACCAACCCAAGCACAGGACACCUGUUUGAUCUGAGCUCCUUAAGUGGCAGGGCGGGAUUCACAGCUGCUUACAGCGAGAAGGGGUUGGUUUACAUGAGCAUCUGUGGGGAGAAUGAAAACUGCCCUCCUGGCGUGGGGGCCUGCUUUGGACAGACCAGGAUUAGCGUGGGCAAGGCCAACAAGAGGCUGAGAUACGUGGACCAGGUCCUGCAGCUGGUGUACAAGGAUGGGUCCCCUUGUCCCUCCAAAUCCGGCCUGAGCUAUAAGAGUGUGAUCAGUUUCGUGUGCAGGCCUGAGGCCAGGCCAACCAAUAGGCCCAUGCUCAUCUCCCUGGACAAGCAGACAUGCACUCUCUUCUUCUCCUGGCACACGCCGCUGGCCUGCGAGCAAGCGACCGAAUGUUCCGUGAGGAAUGGAAGCUCUAUUGUUGACUUGUCUCCCCUUAUUCAUCGCACUGGUGGUUAUGAGGCUUAUGAUGAGAGUGAGGAUGAUGCCUCCGAUACCAACCCUGAUUUCUACAUCAAUAUUUGUCAGCCACUAAAUCCCAUGCACGGAGUGCCCUGUCCUGCCGGAGCCGCUGUGUGCAAAGUUCCUAUUGAUGGUCCCCCCAUAGAUAUCGGCCGGGUAGCAGGACCACCAAUACUCAAUCCAAUAGCAAAUGAGAUUUACUUGAAUUUUGAAAGCAGUACUCCUUGCUUAGCGGACAAGCAUUUCAACUACACCUCGCUCAUCGCGUUUCACUGUAAGAGAGGUGUGAGCAUGGGAACGCCUAAGCUGUUAAGGACCAGCGAGUGCGACUUUGUGUUCGAAUGGGAGACUCCUGUCGUCUGUCCUGAUGAAGUGAGGAUGGAUGGCUGUACCCUGACAGAUGAGCAGCUCCUCUACAGCUUCAACUUGUCCAGCCUUUCCACGAGCACCUUUAAGGUGACUCGCGACUCGCGCACCUACAGCGUUGGGGUGUGCACCUUUGCAGUCGGGCCAGAACAAGGAGGCUGUAAGGACGGAGGAGUCUGUCUGCUCUCAGGCACCAAGGGGGCAUCCUUUGGACGGCUGCAAUCAAUGAAACUGGAUUACAGGCACCAGGAUGAAGCGGUCGUUUUAAGUUACGUGAAUGGUGAUCGUUGCCCUCCAGAAACCGAUGACGGCGUCCCCUGUGUCUUCCCCUUCAUAUUCAAUGGGAAGAGCUACGAGGAGUGCAUCAUAGAGAGCAGGGCGAAGCUGUGGUGUAGCACAACUGCGGACUACGACAGAGACCACGAGUGGGGCUUCUGCAGACACUCAAACAGCUACCGGACAUCCAGCAUCAUAUUUAAGUGUGAUGAAGAUGAGGACAUUGGGAGGCCACAAGUCUUCAGUGAAGUGCGUGGGUGUGAUGUGACAUUUGAGUGGAAAACAAAAGUUGUCUGCCCUCCAAAGAAGUUGGAGUGCAAAUUCGUCCAGAAACACAAAACCUACGACCUGCGGCUGCUCUCCUCUCUCACCGGGUCCUGGUCCCUCGUCCACAACGGAGUCUCGUACUAUAUAAAUCUGUGCCAGAAAAUAUAUAAAGGGCCCCUGGGCUGCUCUGAAAGGGCCAGCAUUUGCAGAAGGACCACAACUGGUGACGUCCAGGUCCUGGGACUCGUUCACACGCAGAAGCUGGGUGUCAUAGGUGACAAAGUUGUUGUCACGUACUCCAAAGGUUAUCCGUGUGGUGGAAAUAAGACCGCAUCCUCCGUGAUAGAAUUGACCUGUACAAAGACGGUGGGCAGACCUGCAUUCAAGAGGUUUGAUAUCGACAGCUGCACUUACUACUUCAGCUGGGACUCCCGGGCUGCCUGCGCCGUGAAGCCUCAGGAGGUGCAGAUGGUGAAUGGGACCAUCACCAACCCUAUAAAUGGCAAGAGCUUCAGCCUCGGAGAUAUUUAUUUUAAGCUGUUCAGAGCCUCUGGGGACAUGAGGACCAAUGGGGACAACUACCUGUAUGAGAUCCAACUUUCCUCCAUCACAAGCUCCAGAAACCCGGCGUGCUCUGGAGCCAACAUAUGCCAGGUGAAGCCCAACGAUCAGCACUUCAGUCGGAAAGUUGGAACCUCUGACAAGACCAAGUACUACCUUCAAGACGGCGAUCUCGAUGUCGUGUUUGCCUCUUCCUCUAAGUGCGGAAAGGAUAAGACCAAGUCUGUUUCUUCCACCAUCUUCUUCCACUGUGACCCUCUGGUGGAGGACGGGAUCCCCGAGUUCAGUCACGAGACUGCCGACUGCCAGUACCUCUUCUCUUGGUACACCUCAGCCGUGUGUCCUCUGGGGGUGGGCUUUGACAGCGAGAAUCCCGGGGACGACGGGCAGAUGCACAAGGGGCUGUCAGAACGGAGCCAGGCAGUCGGCGCGGUGCUCAGCCUGCUGCUGGUGGCGCUCACCUGCUGCCUGCUGGCCCUGUUGCUCUACAAGAAGGAGAGGAGGGAAACAGUGAUAAGUAAGCUGACCACUUGCUGUAGGAGAAGUUCCAACGUGUCCUACAAAUACUCAAAGGUGAAUAAGGAAGAAGAGACAGAUGAGAAUGAAACAGAGUGGCUGAUGGAAGAGAUCCAGCUGCCUCCUCCACGGCAGGGAAAGGAAGGGCAGGAGAACGGCCAUAUUACCACCAAGUCAGUGAAAGCCCUCAGCUCCCUGCAUGGGGAUGACCAGGACAGUGAGGAUGAGGUUCUGACCAUCCCAGAGGUGAAAGUUCACUCGGGCAGGGGAGCUGGGGCAGAGAGCUCCCACCCAGUGAGAAACGCACAGAGCAAUGCCCUUCAGGAGCGUGAGGACGAUAGGGUGGGGCUGGUCAGGGGUGAGAAGGCGAGGAAAGGGAAGUCCAGCUCUGCACAGCAGAAGACAGUGAGCUCCACCAAGCUGGUGUCCUUCCAUGACGACAGCGACGAGGACCUCUUACACAUCUGACUCCGCAGUGCCUGCAGGGGAGCACGGAGCCGCGGGACAGCCAAGCACCUCCAACCAAAUAAGACUUCCACUCGAUGAUGCUUCUAUAAUUUUGCCUUUAACAGAAACUUUCAAAAGGGAAGAGUUUUUGUGAUGGGGGAGAGGGUGAAGGAGGUCAGGCCCCACUCCUUCCUGAUUGUUUACAGUCAUUGGAAUAAGGCAUGGCUCAGAUCGGCCACAGGGCGGUACCUUGUGCCCAGGGUUUUGCCCCAAGUCCUCAUUUAAAAGCAUAAGGCCGGACGCAUCUCAAAACAGAGGGCUGCAUUCGAAGAAACCCUUGCUGCUUUAGUCCCGAUAGGGUAUUUGACCCCGAUAUAUUUUAGCAUUUUAAUUCUCUCCCCCUAUUUAUUGACUUUGACAAUUACUCAGGUUUGAGAAAAAGGAAAAAAAAACAGCCACCGUUUCUUCCUGCCAGCAGGGGUGUGAUGUACCAGUUUGUCCAUCUUGAGAUGGUGAGGCUGUCAGUGUAUGGGGCAGCUUCCGGCGGGAUGUUGAACUGGUCAUUAAUGUGUCCCCUGAGUUGGAGCUCAUUCUGUCUCUUUUCUCUUUUGCUUUCUGUUUCUUAAGGGCACACACACGUGCGUGCGAGCACACACACACAUACGUGCACAGGGUCCCCGAGUGCCUAGGUUUUGGAGAGUUUGCCUGUUCUAUGCCUUUAGUCAGGAAUGGCUGCACCUUUUUGCAUGAUAUCUUCAAGCCUGGGCGUACAGAGCACAUUUGUCAGUAUUUUUGCCGGCUGGUGAAUUCAAACAACCUGCCCAAAGAUUGAUUUGUGUGUUUGUGUGUGUGUGUGUGUGUGUGUGUGUGUGUGUGAGUGGAGUUGAGGUGUCAGAGAAAAUGAAUUUUUUCCAGAUUUGGGGUAUAGGUCUCAUCUCUUCAGGUUCUCAUGAUACCACCUUUACUGUGCUUAUUUUUUUAAGAAAAAAGUGUUGAUCAACCAUUCGACCUAUAAGAAGCCUUAAUUUGCACAGUGUGUGACUUACAGAAACUGCAUGAAAAAUCAUGGGCCAGAGCCUCGGCCCUAGCAUUGCACUUGGCCUCAUGCUGGAGGGAGGCUGGGCGGGUACAGCGCGGAGGAGGAGGGAGGCCAGGCGGGCAUGGCGUGGAGGAGGAGGGAGGCCGGGCGGUCACAGCAUGGAGGAGGAGGGAGGCGCUGCUGGUGUUCUUAUUCUGGCGGCAGCGCCUUUCCUGCCAUGUUUAGUGAAUGACUUUUCUCGCAUUGUAGAAUUGUAUAUAGACUCUGGUGUUCUAUUGCUGAGAAGCAAACCGCCCUGCAGCAUCCCUCAGCCUGUACCGGUUUGGCUGGCUUGUUUGAUUUCAACAUGAGUGUAUUUUUUAAAAUUGAUUUUUCUCUUCAUUUUUUUUUCAAUCAACUUUACUGUAAUAUAAAGUAUUCAACAAUUUCAAUAAAAGAUAAAUUAUUAAUUGGGUGUUACCAUUUUUUCCUUGAUAGUGAGACGUUCCCGAGCGAGUUACCCAUCUGCCUGCCUGUCUUUUCUUUCUGUUAAGUGACUGAAUUUGGGUUUUAACUCUGGUGUUCUCGUUGACCCUUUAUGAGGCAGCACUUUCAUUUUUCUCCAGAGUCUCCUGGUCGUAGGUGUUAACUUUGGGUCCAAUCUGCCUUCCCUUGGCUCUUUCUAGAUCCGAUUUCUUUACCUUCUCCAGGCCAACCUCGGGGUGUGGUCCUGUUCAUCAAAACAAUGAACAUGGAGUUUAGAGUCCAGUGAGUCAAUAAAGCUUUUUUUUGUGCAACCUGAUCUAACAUGGAGAUGUUUUCUCUUGAGUAAACUCACUGAGUUUUCCAUCUUAAAUUACUCAGCAGUGACUGAGAGCUACCUGCAUGGAAGCAGGAAGUUACUCCAGUGUUAUAAACAAACUUCUUAGACUCAACAUCCUAUUCUCCAUCCCUUUUUUUUUCCUGUAGAGUCCAAAAACCUCAACCGUCUCAUUUUUAAAUUAUCCAAUUGGAGUUACCUUUUUAAAAAAGUUAUUCUUAAGGACUUUCCAAUACCUCUCCUGAGGAAGACAUGUCAGGUCUUCUAAAAGUUUACAUUAUGACCAAAGAAAGAUGCUGGUCCUCAGGCAUUCUACCCAGGGGGCUGUUCUCCAGGCCAUUCCCACCUCCUGCUAAGACCAUGGGGAGCCCUCUCUGUAAGGAGGGGCAUAUGCAGGGACCUGCCCAUCCCCUUGGUAAGCUGGAUGGCAAAAAGGCAUGUUGUCUGCACCACUGGCUGCCUGCUAAUGUCGCUGUCAGUGGGGAAGGAGAAGUGACAACACGUUUGAGUGCAUUUGCUUUGACUCUUAGAAACCCAAGCCUCUGAAAAAAGAGUAACUACUUGCCAGCUGUUGUUACAGAUGAUAUUUUUAGGAAAACAUCCCGUGACAGCAAAUCAGAAUUGGACUCUUUUUCAGAGAAAUGAUUUUAUUGAUGGAGUACAACCUGGGUAUUUAGCUUCCUUUCAACAAAAUUUUUUGUGCCCCUUUCUUGAGACUGUCCAUGAAUGACAGAGACAUAGAAUAAGAACUGGGGUGCUAAAGAUGGAAUAGGCAAACCCCACACCAAGGAAAUCCACAGUGAAGUGGAAAUCUGGUUCUUAUGAACAUUUUAAGAGCAUCUGAAGCCUGUACUUCACCAACCCUAAAAUAAUACGUAACACGAGAUGAUUCCUCAGGAAGGAACAUAUAGACAUACAGACAGGAGACAACAUAUAGACAUUAGAACUUACAGGACAAAGAACUCUUUUUCCCUGAAUCAUUUGAGAUGAAGUUUCUUCCCAUCACCAGGCAUUCCUACAAACAAGGACCUUCACACGACUAAGAUGCCACCUGGUGAUUAAAGAACACUUUGGGCUGGUCCGAUCCAUUGUACAAGUUAAAGCACUGAUGGGUACACAGGUCUUACCCCUGUUGGCGAUCGGGUCACAAGGAGCCAGUGUGUGUGUCACCAGGAGGUUGUAUGGACGAGACUGGAUUUCUGGAAAUAUCCUUUACUGACUCUGAAGAAUCCCAUGGCUCAGGGAGGUACACUCAUGUCCUUUCUUACUUCUCCGGUUCCACUCUGUUGACUAGUAGUUGGCCUCUUGAGCCAUACUUGCUGUCAGUUCUGGACAUUGUUCUGUGAGAAUGGGGUCAACGGGCAGUCGUGGUGCAGGUGAGCUUGUGUGCAAGGCGGCAAGAUAGCCACAUUGAGUUGGGGACAGUAUGGCCUGGGGGUGUUGGAUAGGUAAGGCAGAAGCAAGCCCAGAACUUGGAGCCUGUUGUGACUGUCACAGUAAGGAGUUUGAAGUCCUGAAAGCAGUUGAGAGCUGUAGGAGGGCCAGAUUGGGCUUUUGAGCAAGAUAGUCUAGAUGAAAGUAAAGAGAUGGAGACGCUUCAGCAACCAGAUGGGAGGUUGGGCAUGGGAGCUGUGGCUGUGCUGAGCUGAGAAGCCUCAGACUGCCUGCGAGGCUCUCUCUGGGAGGAAGUCAGGUCUUUCUUUCCUUCGUUUCCUUCCUUUCAUUCCUUUCCUUUCCUUCCUUUUUCCUCUUUCUUUCUUUCCUUUUCUCUCUCUCUCUUUUUCUUUCUCUCUUUCUUUCGAGAUGGAGUCUCGCUCUGUUGCCAGGCUGGAGUGCAGUGGCAUGAUCUCGGCUCACUGCAAUCUCUGCCUCCCGGGUUCAAGGGAUUCUCCUGCCUCAGCCUCCCUAGUAGCUGGGAUUAAAGGCACGCACUGCCACGCCCGGCUAAUUUUUGUAUUUUUAAUAGCGACAGGGUUUCACCGUGUUGGCCAGGAUGGUCUCGAUCUCCUGACCUCAUGAUCCACCUGCCUCGGCCUCCGAAAGUGCUGGGAUUACAGGCGUGAGCCACCGUGCCCAGCCAGGUCUUUUUCUUAAAGAGGGACAGACUGAAGGUAGGCUGUGAAUGGUCAGUUAUUUGUAUUUCUUUACCUUUUAUGCUAUCUUGUAGUUUGACCAGUUUGCAAAACAAAUUGAAUAAAAAGUAAUUGAUAAUGUUGUUUUGAUGCUCAGUGUUUGAGGGAAACACAAUCUAGUGAAUGGGGUUAUUGGUUGUCACACCUGGGAGAGUGAAAAUGAGGGGCUCACAACCCAGGUGAGGUCAUCUGGUGCCACUCAGCCCCAUCCCAGAGAAAGCAGCCUUGGGAUGCUGGCCUCGGUGACAACCAAGAAGUGAUGGUGGGUUGCUAGAGACAGGGUGGAGCACAGAGCCCUGGAAGGAAGCAGGAAGUCAGGUUCAAGAAAGGACUUGUGACCUCACCCUUGGCUUCAGGGUUUUAUUUUUCUUUCUUUUAAAACAUUUUGAGACAACAUGUAGACAUUCAAACUUACAGAACAAAGAACUAUUUUUUCCCUGAAUCAUUUGAGACUAAGUUCCCUCCUAUCACCAGACAUUUCUACAAAUGAGGACCUUCACAGGACUAAGGUGCCACCAUCAGAACCACAAUAUGUGGGGACGGUACUGCCAGCUAAGCCUUAGUGCUGUUUCGGUGUUGACAGCUGUCACAAUGAUGCCCUUUUCAGUAGAGGAGCCUGUGAUGGUCACGUGUUGCAGGUGAUCAUUGUGCCAUUUGGUUUACUUCUGUCUGGAAAGUUUCUCCUUUCUGUAACCUCCAUGACCUUGACACAUGAGGUCACUCUUCUCACCCGCCCCACCUCUGGGAGGGUGCCUGAUUUGCCCUGCCCCACCCAGCGGCUUUAGGACUCAGCUCUUCAGGAACAAUUAGGGAGAGGGCCCUUGGGUCUAACUGCAAAAUCAUACUUGAACUAGAAAAUCCCGUUGGCAUAGGUAUGGAUUGUCAUAUAGAAACAUUUUUCGCAGUGUGCCCCGUGGAACACUUGUUCUGUAUGUUGUUAACAGAUGUUUUGCAAAAAAUGAAAAGGACCUGAGCUCUAAUAAGUUUGGGAAAUGCUGAAUUGAAGUGAAACAGCUUUUCUUGGUGUGAGACCUUUCAGAGUCUUUAAAGGAGAGUUGCUGACCACACGUGAAAUCACAAUAGAAAAUGGCCAGCAGGCCUCCAGGUAGGCAGCAAUUCCUAGACAUUUGCCUGUGUUCCCUGGGGGAGCUGGUGGCCUGUGACCAUCCACUGGGAAAUUCCCUUCUGUGGCGAGGUUCUGUUGUUUUCCAGAGGCUCCCACGGAGCAUGCUGGGUGGGUGGUCUGUAUGAGACCACACCGUUGAUGAGCAGUGAGGCCCAAACAGGUAUAUCAAAAAAUGCUCAGCAUCGCUGAUCAUCAGGGAAAUGCACAUCAUAAACACAGUGAGACGUUGCCUCACACCUGCCAGAAUGGCUACUGUCAGACGAAAGACAACAAGUGUGGGUGAGGAUGUGGAGAAAAGCGAACACUUGUCCACCUUUGGUGAGAAUGUAAAUUGGUAUAGCCAUUAUGGAAAACAGGAAGUUCCUGAAAAAAUUAAGAACAGCUACCAGGAAUCCCACAUCUGGGUGUAUAUCCAAAAGAAAUGAAGUCAGUACCUUGAAGAGAUCUCUGCAGCCCCUGUUCAUUGCAGCAUUAUUCACAAUAGCCAAGAUAGGGAAAAAGCCUCAGUGUCUACUGACAAAUAAAGAUGGAUCAAGAAAAUGCAUGUAUGUAUACACACACACAGUGGAAUACCAAGUCUUGCAGAAGAAGGAAAUCCUGUCAUUUGUGACAACAUGGAUGAGCUGAGAGAACAUUAUGCUAAGUGAAAUAAGCCAGACACAGAAAGAAAAAUACCAGAUGAUCUCACUUAUAUGUGGAAUCUAAAAAGGUUGGACUCAGAAGCAGAGAGUGGAAUGGUGGUUACCAAAGGCCAGAGGGUGCAGGAAGUGAGCAGAUGUUGGUGAAAGGGUGCAGAGGUUCAGCUAUGCAACAUGAAUGAAUUCUGGAGAUCCACUGUGCAGCAUGGUGACUAUGAUACUGCUUUGUGUAUUUAAAAUUUUCAGAGAGUAGAUCUUGUGUUCUUUCCCCUCUCCAAAUAAAAGGAAAUUAUUUGAGGUGAUGGAUAUGUUUAACUAGCUUGACUGGGGCAAUGAUUUUGUAAUGAUAAGUAUCUCAAAACAUCAUGUUGUACAACAUAAGUAUACAAUUGACCCUUGAACAAUACAGGUUUGAACUCUGUGGGUCCACUUACAUGCGGUUUUUUUUUUCUGUAAAAGUUACACCCGAUGCGUCAGCCCCUUCUUCUACCUCUUCCACCUCUGGCACCCUUGGCACAGCAAGACCAACCCCCCACUUCCUCCUCCUCCUCCUCAGCCUACUCAGGGUAAAGACAAGGAUGAAGACCUUUAUGAUGAUCCACUUCCACUUAAUAUAUAAUAAAUAUAUUUUCUCCUCAUGAUUUUCUUAAAACUUUUUCUGUAUUUUAUUGUAAGAAUACAGUAUAUAAUACAUACAACAUCGAAAA